AUGAGCUCCCCUUCCCACACCCCUAAUCCAUCCCCUACCCAGUCUCCCUCCCAGUCCCGUUCCAACAACAUUGUCACCCCUCCAGGCCAGCAGCCUGCCCCUUCCCCCUCCCCCACUCGGGGCUCUUCCUCCCGGCCCCCCUCCCACCCUCCCACCCCAAAUGCCUCACAGCCCUCUUCCCGGACUUCGUCCCUGAACCCCAGUCCUCAGGUCCAACACGUGCCCCGCGGGGCUGCCCAAACCCCCACCCCACCCACCUCCAAAUCUCCCUCCCAGUCUGGUUUCAAAUCCCUCUCUCGAAACCCUUCCCUAACCCCCGCUGUGCCCCCCAAGUCCUCCUUCUACAGCCCUGCCACCUCAUCUUCCUAUAUCGGGCCAAUUCAGAACAUCCCGUCCUAUAUCACCCCCUAUGUGCCCCGCUUUCUGAAGGAGCCCCCCUUUUUCCAGCCCCCCACAGCACCACUUCCCCAAAACCCAUGCUUUGCCUGUCCCUCUCCCUGCCCUGCCCGGAAGCCCCCACCCCCUCCUGACUCACUCUACUUACCUCUCCUUCCCCCGCCCCCCCACCACCCCCAGUUUAACUGCCCCUUCCCAACUCCCCCCGGUCUGUUCAUGCCCCCCUCCUCUCUCUCCUACACCCCGCCCGUGGAGGUCCUGGUGAGCGGGAAGCCGCACGUGGUCCCCAACGUACUGCCUGCCACCUUCUACACCCCCUUCUCCCGCUACUACUCCCAGCCCCGCUCCUACCGCUCAGGGUACCGCGGCUACUCCGGCGCCCUGACCCUCCCCUCCAUCUCCCCCUUGCAAUACGACGGCUCUGGGCGCUCUGUCCACUUCUAUCAUGGGUCCUAG